AGUGCGCGCCUAGCAGUGUCCCAGCCGGGUUCGUGUCGCCAUGGGGCAGAUCGAGUGGGCCAUGUGGGCCAACGAACAGGCGCUGGCGUCCGGCCUGAUCCUCAUCACCGGGGGCAUCGUGGCCACAGCUGGGCGCUUCACCCAGUGGUACUUUGGUGCCUACUCCAUUGUGGCGGGCGUGUUUGUGUGCCUGCUGGAGUACCCCCGGGGGAAGAGGAAGAAGGGCUCCACCAUGGAGCGCUGGGGACAGAAGUACAUGACCGCCGUGGUGAAGCUGUUCGGGCCCUUUACCAGGAAUUACUAUGUUCGGGCCGUCCUGCAUCUCCUGCUCUCGGUGCCCGCCGGCUUCCUGCUGGCCACCAUCCUUGGGACCGCCUGCCUGGCCAUUGCGAGCGGCAUCUACCUACUGAGCCAAGUCCCUCCUGCCCGCAGAGGCAACUGCCCUCCCCUUGCUGUGCGUCUUCUAGUGUGUGUGCGUGGGAAAGGUGCAGCACUUUCUGUGUACGCCUUCCGCGUAUGGAAGUGGAGUUCUGUUUCAAGCCUCACUGACCUGCCACCGGCAGAACUCUCCUUUAGAACCCCUUCCUGUUGCCAAGUGCUCAUCUGGGCUGUUGCUUUGUUUUCCGGGGGCCACCCGCAUCCCCCCCGUCUCCCUGCUGCCACGCACAGCUAGUGGCUCCUGGAGACCUCGGGAGGAAUUCCUUGUGCUAAACCCAGAGAGGAAUUGCUGGGUCAGGCAUCAGCCUCUGCACCGUUCACCCUGCCGGGCUCAGCUGCUCCUCAGCAGACAACCCACCACCAGCCAUGUGGCCCCAUCUCUCCCACCAUGCACUAGGCUUUCUCCCACGCUUGCCAGUUUCACAGCACGAGCUGGCCGUGUGGAGCUUGGACUCGCCCUUCUCUGACUGUGGAUUUGAGCUGUUGGAGUUUCUUCUCCCUUGAGUUGCCUGUUCAAAUCCUUUGCCCAUUUUUCUAUUGUGGUUUUUGUAUUUUUCUUUUUCUUCUUUUUUUUUUGAGAUGGAGUCUCGCGCCAUCGCCCAGGCUGGAGUGCAGUGGCGUGAUCUCGGCUCACUGCAACCUUCGCCUCCUGGGUUCAAGCAAUUCUCCUGCCUCAGCCUCCCGAGUAGCUGGGACUACAGGCACGUGCCACCAUGCCUGGCUAAUUUUUGGUAUUUUUAGUAGAGACGGGGUUUCACCGCGUUAGCCAGGAUGGUCUGGAUCUCCUUGACCUUGUGAUCCGCCCGCCUCGGCCUCCCAAAGUGCUGGGAUUACAGGCGUGAGCCACCGCGCCCGGCCUGAUUGUCUUUUUCUUAAGUUGCAGGAAGUCCACAUAUAUUUUAGCUAUUUAGCCUUUGUAACCUUUAAACACUGGGGAUGCCUUCAUGCUUUCUGGUGAGGGUCUGUUAACUUGGCGCGUGGAGUCCUUCACUGCACGGAAGAGCAGAGGUUUCCCUGUUCACCUGCUCUAUGGUCUGUGCUUUGUGAAAACACCUUUCCCUGGCCCUGGGUCCUGCCUUCACGUUCCUGCCUUUUCUUCUAUCAGCCUUCUAGUUUUGCUUUUCAGAAUGGAAUGUUUCCGUUUUGGAGUCAGGUAGGAUCACACAUGUCCAGUUUCUCUUUCUGUUCAUGACGUAUAUGAUGUGACAUAUUUUUCCACCAGAUAUUAUGGGAUAGAAGAUGAAAAGCACACACUCCCAGGUCCACUUGACCUGUUGCAGUGGAACCUCCGGGCAUGGGCCCAGGAGUCUGUAUUUUUAGUAAAAGCCAGUGGAAUCCCGUGGUCUUCAAGCUCUCCCCCCACCACCCCCAUGUGCAGAAAUGCCUGGGCACCCUUGGGGGGCUGCCGGCCAGCGUGGGUGAAUGGCGCCCACCAGACGGAGCAGGGCCUGCUACUCUCCUGGGCCACCCCUCCUGCUGGACCUCGGGCCUGCCUCCCUGCCUUCCCUGCCCUUGGCACCUUGAGAGGAGAAUUUGAGUACUAGAAUUUGCAUCUGGGAGUGUCCACCACGGGAUCUUCCAGAAGCCCAGGGGUUCGGGCCCCACUCCUGGCAUGAAGAAAUAGCUUGGGCUGGUGUCAGGCCGACCCAGGUCCUGGCUGUGUGGCCUCGGGCGCGUCACUUAACCUCUCUGAGUGGCAGUCACACCAUCCUGCGUGGGAUUCAGACUUGAGCCUGUCCCAGGGCCCCUAGCGGGGUGGGCCUCCGGGGAGGGAGGGAGGGAGGGAGGGCGGGCGCUGGGGCGCGGCUCAACCCUUCAGUGCCCCGCAGGCGGCUGUGCGUGGCGAGCAGUGGACGCCCAUCGAGCCCAAGCCCCGGGAGCGGCCGCAGAUCGGAGGCACCAUCAAGCAGCCGCCCAGCAACCCCCCGCCGCGGCCCCCGGCCGAGGCCCGCAAGAAGCCCAGCGAGGAGGAGGCUGCGGUGGCGGCGGGGGGACCCCCGGGAGGUCCCCAGGUCAACCCCAUCCCGGUGACCGACGAGGUCGUGUGACCUCGCCCCGGACCUGCCCUCCCGCCAGGUGCACCCACCUGCAAUAAAUGCAGCGAAGCCGGGA